GCUACCUCUCAAUACCGCCACCUCCCAACACUGCCAUCUCCCGAUACCCACAUCUCCCAAUACUGCUACCUCUCAAUACCACCACCUCCAACACCACCAUCUCCAACACUGCCACCUCCAACACCACCAUCUCCAACACCGCCACCUCCAACACCGCCGUCUCCCGAUACCUCCACCUCCGGACACCCCCACCUCCUGACCCACCCACCUCCCAACACCAACACCUCCCGACACACCCACCUCCCGACACCCCCACCUCCCAAUACCAACACCUCCCGACACCCCCACUUCCCGACACCCCCACCUCCCGACACCAACACCUCCCAACACCAACACUUCCCCACACCCCCACCUCCCAACACUAACACCUCCUGACACCCCCACCUCCCGACACCCCCACCUCCCAACACCAACACCUCCCGACACCCCCACCUCCCGACACCAACACCUCCCGACACCAACACCUCCCGACACCAACACCUCACGACACCCACACCUCCCGACACCAACACCUCCCGACACCAACACCUUCCGACACCCCCACCUCCCGACACCGCCACCUCCCGAUACCCGCAUCUCCCGACACCACCAUCUCUGGCAUUAAGUUCCUGGUGCAUUUUGGAGGGGACGCACCCAACCAGAGCAGAGACCUGUGAGUGUCCAUCACUCGCACAUUGUCAUACACUAGUUGCCAUGUCCAUGGAUGACUUCUGCCGCCCUCACCCUCUGGGCAUCAGUCAUCCUGCCGUGACUCCGAACCUUCCCUCCUUGCCUGUCUUCUUACUGAUUUGUUUCUGUCCGUGUGCAUGAGGCUUCUGUCUUAUUCCCGGGUUAUCAUUCAUUAUCAUUUAUCCCAGUGCUCAAAUCGUCCCACAUGGACCCUCAGGAGUCCCUCCGAACAAUCCCUGUGUCCUUGUAAUGCACCUGCUGUCCUCUGAACCUGCUCUUACUGUGGGGCACAUGGUACCGCAGGCUCGGCCUCUGAGCCCGCGCUUACUGUGGGGCGCGCGGUACCGCAGGCUCGGCCUCUGAGCCCACUCUUACUGUUGGACAUGUGAUGUCGCAGGCUCGUCCCAUGCUCUCCCUGCCCCAGCCCUCAGAUGCUCCAUUUCUUGGAGGAGACCUGGCGCCUUUGAGUGGAGGGUGACUUAGGCACCGGAUGUGUUCACCACUGCCAGGGAGCAGCAUUCCUGGGCACCGUUAACAGUUAGGAAGCAGACACGCAUCUCUGCACCACACAUGGACACACACACUCUUCUAUUCUGUGUCUGUAUAUCAAAUCCACAAGUGCAGCGGGGCAUGCCGGCACACACCUGAGGUCCCAGCCACUCGGGAGGCUGAGGCAGGGGGAUUGCUUGAGUCUGGGAGUUCAGGGCCACAGUGAACGUGAACUAUGCAUUCGUGAACUAUCCAUUGCAGCCUGGGCAACAGAGCAAGACCCUUUUUCUAAAAAAAUAAAAACUUCCAGGAGUCCACUUUGCAGCUUCUCUUCCAGUCCAGCGCUGCUGGGCCCCCCAGCUGUCUCCCUUGCUGUCCUUUAACUCCCGUCUCCGACCGCCAGCCGUCACUCCUGGGUGACACACUGUCGAGAUGGAGAGCUGCUGUUUGAAGGCCCGUGGUCCUUGGAAAGGACGAUGUGCAGGUCCCGGGAGGCCUCCCCCUCAUGCUGCAGUCACUCGGCAGACAAUUGCCAGGCCCACGCUGGUGCUGGGGUACAAACGGGAAGGCGGGGGCUCUGCCGGCCACAGGACUCUCAGCUCCCUCAUCACCACCCACACCCACGGGCUGGCCUCCCAAAAUUUCCCCCAUCUGCCUCUGGCCCCCCAACCGGAUCAUUCUUUCCACCCUUGCCUCCCUGGGGUCCCCGUGAGCUCCCGAUCAUUCUUUCCACCCCUACUGCCCUGGGGUCGGGGUGAGCUCCCAAUCAUUCUUUCCACCCUGACCGCCCUGGGGUCGGCGUGAGCUCCCGAUCGUUCUUUCUACCCCUACUGCUCUGGGGUCCGUGUGAGCUCCGGAUCAUUCUUUCCACCCUGACUCCCCUGGGGUCGGAGUGAGCUCCCGAUCAUUCUUUCCACUCUGACCGCCCUGGGGUUGAGGUGAACCAGUCUUUGCAUUGAAGCUGCAAGCCUGAGGCACGGUGGCCCUGGCGUCUCCCGAGCCAUGAGUGGCCGGGCCACCCUUCCCGCCACCCUCCUCCCUUCACACAUGAGGAGGGCUCCCCGAGGACUUUCUGAACUCCCUGGAGAAGAUGGAGGACGGCAAGUUGAAGGUCACCCUCAAGUACCCCCAUUACUUCCCCCUCCUGAAGAAAUGCCACGUGCCUGAGACCAGGAGGAAAGUGGAGGAGGCCUUCAACUGCCGGUGCAAGGAGGAGAACUGCGCUAUCCUCAAGGAGCUGGUGACGCUGCGGGCCCAGAAGUCCCGCCUGCUGGGGUUCCACACGCACGCCGACUAUGUCCUGGAGAUGAACAUGGCCAAGACCAGCCAGACCGUGGCCACCUUCCUAGAUGAGCUGGCGCAGAAGCUGAAGCCCCUGGGGGAGCAGGAGCGUGCGGUGAUUCUGGAGCUGAAGCGUGCGGAGUGCGAGCGCCGGGGCCUGCCCUUCGACGGCCGCAUCCGUGCCUGGGACAUGCGCUACUACAUGAACCAGGUGGAGGAGACGCGCUACUGCGUGGACCAGAACCUGCUCAAGGAGUACUUCCCCGUGCAGGUGGUCACGCACGGGCUGCUGGGCAUCUACCAGGAGCUCCUGGGGCUGGCCUUCCACCACGAGGAGGGCGCCAGUGCCUGGCAUGAGGACGUGCGGCUCUACACCGCGAGGGACGCGGCCUCGGGGGAGGUGGUCGGCAAGUUCUACCUGGACCUGUACCCGCGGGAAGGAAAGUACGGGCACGCGGCCUGCUUUGGCCUGCAGCCCGGCUGCCUGCGGCAGGAUGGGAGCCGCCAGAUCGCCAUCGCGGCCAUGGUGGCCAACUUCACCAAGCCCACAGCCGACGCGCCCUCGCUGCUGCAGCAUGACGAGGUGGAGACCUACUUCCAUGAGUUUGGCCACGUGAUGCACCAGCUCUGCUCCCAGGCGGAGUUCGCCAUGUUCAGCGGGACCCACGUGGAGCGGGACUUUGUGGAGGCGCCGUCGCAGAUGCUGGAGAACUGGGUGUGGGAGCAGGAGCCGCUGCUGCGGAUGUCGCGGCACUACCGCACAGGCAGCGCCGUGCCCCGGGAGCUCCUGGAGAAGCUCAUUGAGUCCCGGCAGGCCAACACAGGCCUCUUCAACCUGCGCCAGAUCGUCCUCGCCAAGGUGGACCAGGCCCUGCACACGCAGACGGACGCAGACCCCGCCGAGGAGUAUGCGCGGCUCUGCCAGGAGAUCCUCGGGGUCCCGGCCACGCCAGGAACCAACAUGCCUGCAACCUUCGGCCAUCUGGCAGGUGGCUACGACGCCCAGUACUACGGGUACCUGUGGAGCGAGGUGUAUUCCAUGGACAUGUUCCACACGCGCUUCAAGCAGGAGGGUGUCCUGAACAGCAAGGUUGGCAUGGAUUACAGAAGCUGCAUCCUGAGACCCGGCGGUUCCGAGGAUGCCAGCGCCAUGCUGAGGCGCUUCCUGGGCCGUGACCCCAAGCAGGACGCCUUCCUCCUGAGCAAGGGGCUGCAGGUCGGGGGCUGCGAGCCCGAGCCGCAGGUCUGCUGAGGCCUGGCACUGCGACUGCCCAGUCUGGCCUGCGCUCCCGCCGCCCUGGUGCCUUAGCCCCCGGCACAGGAUGGGGCAGGCUCUGGCACAGUGCCUGGGACUGGCAGGGUGGCUGAGCGGCUGUCUUGCCUCUUGUCAUUGUCUGUCCCCACCCGGUCGUGGCCCACCCGGCUAGAGACGGCGUCCUCAAGGCAUCUGGAGGGCUUUCGUGGCUGCCAGGGCCUGGUCUUUGUUGCACUAACACGUCUCCUCUCUGGGAAACGUCCCUUGUCAGGAGACGGCUCUUCUUUGAAAUGAGGUCAUUAAAAGGAAACAGAAAAAGAGAGAGGCUCCCUGGCCUGGUCACUGGCUCCUGCGCUUUUUUGGUCCGAGGACGGUGGGACGGCGGGUCAGGGUCCAGCCCUCGGGCUGUUGCCACACCAGGCCCUGGAUUGGGGCUCAGGUCCUUGUGGGGGCGGGGGGUGGGGGAGUAAAGGGCUGGGAACCAGUUCUGCCAGCCAGGCCGGCCUGGGGGGUCUGAGAGACUUCGGCUUCCUGCAUGCUUCUCACCUGUUGUCAUUCUGGAACAUUCCCCCCGCCCUGCUCAGCUCUGGCCAUCAAGGACCAGGCUCCACUGGUCAGAGAGUCUGGAAAGUCAGGGCAGGCCCUGUGCGCACAGGCAGCCGGGGCGGGGCUGGGGGUCAGCAGCUGCCCACCCUCUCAUCCACAGGGGAAGGCCGGGCUCACUCCAGCUUCCUAGGCAGAGUCUCUGGGGGUUCCUGUUGGACACAAGUGAACCAGGUGAACCAGGGCAGCUGCUGGAAGCUCGGCCAUGGCCCUCAUCCUCAUGGCCUUGGGGACUGCCUGUGCCUGCCCUCCCUGGCGGCCCCACUCCCCUGGCUGUGGGCAACAUGGCAAAGUCUUGAUCGGGGGUGCAGGGUCGGGGGGGCGCUUCCUGGACCCUCCAACAGUGCUCAGAGAUGCCUCAGGGAUAGCUGUCGGCUGUGUCCCCACCUCCCGAGCAAGACAAGUGGAUGCUCCCCGUCUCUUCAGUCCCAGUGCUCUGAUGUUUUCUCCCGCGACUGUGAGUUUCUCAGGAGCCCCCCUCGUGCCCUGGGAGCGUCCCUCCCCAGUCUUAGUCCUCCACGAAGGACGCUGGUCAGCAGAACCUGUGACCCUGCUUCCCGAGGCCUAUGGGUGGCCAGACAUCCGCCUCGUCCUCACCUCCAUUUGGACAGGACUCCGAGGGCUGUGCCAUCUGCUUCAGCCCCUCCUGUCCCAUUCCCACCCAGCCCAGGUCAGUGUGGCUGUGGCCACUGCCAUGGGGCCUGCUUUGCACCUUACGCACGCCUGGCUCUGCUCCAUGCACCUGCUUCUGUGUCUUUCCAACUCUGGGGGCUAAGGGGUGAGUCUUGUCUUUGCAGAGCUGGACGGCACAGCCUGUGGCCAGGAGGGUUAUGCCAGCGAGGCGGGAAUCCAUAAGUGGGAACACCACAGUGGUCACGUUUCAGAUACUCACAGCUCAGAGCGGGUCCCAUAGCUUGCACCUGAAGCCCCAACUACUCAGGAGGCUGAGGCGGAAGGAUUGCUUGAGCCCAGGAGGGCAAGGCCAGCCUGGGCAACGUGGCAAGACCCCAUCUCUAAAAAAAAUAAGUUCGGUGGGUGUGGGGCCAGUGCCUGUGGUCUGUUUUUUGGGAGGCUGAGGCAGGAGGAUCGCUUGAGCCUAGGAGGUCAAGGCUGCAGUAAGCCGUGAUCCCACCACUGCACUGCAGCCUGGGCAACAGAGCAAGACUGUCUCUAAAAUAACAAUAAUAAUAAAAUACCUGGGGUUCAGAAAAGAAAAGCUGGAAGGCAAAGCCGACCGCACUGGGCAGAGGUGGAGAUGGCAAGUCUGGGGGCUCCCUCAUCUUCCCCUGCCCCGAGCCCUCAGGUGGCCUCCACCUGGUCCCCAGCGAAGUCCCAGUUGUGCAAGAGCACCCCAGCUGGGCCCUGGGCCAUCACAGCCUUGUCACACACACAGCCUGGCCCAUCACAGCAGAGCUGGGGUCACAGCCUUGGGCUGCUGGGCCGUGGGCGGAUGGCCUGGACCAUCCACACCCCACUCCCCUGGAAGUCACCAACUGGGCUUAGUUGCCGGAUACCCCAGGCAGCCCCCCGCGGUGCUUCGCAAGUUGGGCCGCCUCCCCCAGCAUGUCCCCUGCUCUGUGGACACCCAGGGAUGUGGAGGUAGUAGCACAGAGUCUCGGUCCAGGGCCCUGUUCCCCAGGGAGCUGGGCGUCCUCAGAGCCUUCCCAAAUGCCCACACCGGGGGCACCCGGGUUUCCCCAAACACUCCAGGACAGAGCGGGGGCUUUGAUCACAGGGAGGGGGCUGCAGAGCUGCUGUGUCUCCUGGCUCCUCUGCCCCAUGCUCCCCACUCAGGGCUCCAGCAGUGGGCUCAGAGGACAGUGUGGCAUUAGCAUCCCCUGCCCGUCCAGGUUGUCACUCUCCUUGGCCCCUUGCUGCUCCCCAGUGGAAAAAAAAGGGGGAAAUAAAGAAUCGUAAAAAAUACA